GGUCACAAAUCACAUUAGCUUUGCCCGAAGUUUUUCCCCACACUCUUCUUUAGCAUGCUAUUAUGGGGAAAGUGACCACUCCUGGGAGCGGGGGUGGUCGGGGCGGUUUGGUGGCGGGGAAGCGGCUGUAACUUCUACGUGACCAUGGUACCUGUUGAAAACACCGAGGGCCCCAGUCUGCUGAACCAGAAGGGGACAGCCGUGGAGACGGAGGGCAGCGGCAGCCGGCAUCCUCCCUGGGCGAGAGGCUGCGGCAUGUUUACCUUCCUGUCAUCUGUCACUGCUGCUGUCAGUGGCCUCCUGGUGGGUUAUGAACUUGGGAUCAUCUCUGGGGCUCUUCUUCAGAUCAAAACCUUAUUAGCCCUGAGCUGCCAUGAGCAGGAAAUGGUUGUGAGCUCCCUCGUCAUUGGAGCCCUCCUUGCCUCACUCACCGGAGGGGUCCUGAUAGACAGAUAUGGAAGAAGGACAGCAAUCAUCUUGUCAUCCUGCCUGCUUGGACUCGGAAGCUUAGUCUUGAUCCUCAGUUUAUCCUACACGGUUCUUAUAGUGGGACGCAUUGCCAUAGGGGUCUCCAUCUCCCUCUCUUCCAUUGCCACUUGUGUUUACAUCGCAGAGAUUGCUCCUCAACACAGAAGAGGCCUUCUUGUGUCACUGAAUGAGCUGAUGAUUGUCAUCGGCAUUCUUUCUGCCUAUAUUUCAAAUUACGCAUUUGCCAAUGUUUUCCAUGGCUGGAAGUACAUGUUUGGUCUUGUGAUUCCCUUGGGAGUUUUGCAAGCAAUUGCAAUGUAUUUUCUUCCUCCAAGCCCUCGGUUUCUGGUGAUGAAAGGACAAGAGGGAGCUGCUAGCAAGGUUCUUGGAAGGUUAAGAGCACUCUCAGAUACAACUGAGGAACUCACUGUGAUCAAAUCCUCCCUGAAAGAUGAAUAUCAGUACAGUUUUUGGGAUCUGUUUCGUUCAAAAGACAACAUGCGGACCCGAAUAAUGAUAGGACUAACACUAGUAUUUUUUGUACAAAUCACUGGCCAACCAAACAUAUUGUUCUAUGCAUCAACUGUUUUGAAGUCAGUUGGAUUUCAAAGCAAUGAGGCAGCUAGCCUCGCCUCCACUGGGGUUGGAGUCGUCAAGGUCAUUAGCACCAUCCCUGCCACUCUUCUUGUAGACCAUGUCGGCAGCAAAACAUUCCUCUGCAUUGGCUCCUCUGUGAUGGCAGCUUCGUUGGUGACCAUGGGCAUCGUAAAUCUCAACAUCCACAUGAACUUCACCCAUAUCUGCAGAAGCCACAAUUCUAUCAACCAGUCCUUGGAUGAGUCUGUGAUUUAUGGACCAGGAAACCUGUCAACCAACAACAAUACUCUCAGAGACCACUUCAAAGGGAUUUCUUCCCAUAGCAGAAGCUCACUCAUGCCCCUGAGAAAUGAUGUGGAUAAGAGAGGGGAGACGACCUCAGCAUCCUUGCUAAAUGCUGGAUUAAGCCACACUGAAUACCAGAUAGUCACAGACCCUGGGGACGUCCCAGCUUUUUUGAAAUGGCUGUCCUUAGCCAGCUUGCUUGUUUAUGUUGCUGCUUUUUCAAUUGGUCUAGGACCAAUGCCCUGGCUGGUGCUCAGCGAGAUCUUUCCUGGUGGGAUCAGAGGACGAGCCAUGGCUUUAACUUCUAGCAUGAACUGGGGCAUCAAUCUCCUCAUCUCGCUGACAUUUUUGACUGUAACUGAUCUUAUUGGCCUGCCAUGGGUGUGCUUUAUAUAUACAAUCAUGAGUCUAGCAUCCCUGCUUUUUGUUGUUAUGUUUAUACCUGAGACAAAGGGAUGCUCUUUGGAACAAAUAUCAAUGGAGCUAGCAAAAGUGAACUAUGUGAAAAACAACAUUUGUUUUAUGAGUCAUCACCAAGAAGAAUUAGUGCCAAAACAGCCUCAAAAAAGAAAACCCCAGGAGCAGCUCUUGGAGUGUAACAAGCUGUGUGGUAGGGGCCAAUCCAGGCAGCUUUCUCCAGAGACCUAAUGGCCUCAACACCUUCUGAACGUGGAUAGUGCCAGAACACUUAGGAGGGUGUCUUUGGACCAAUGCAUAGUUGCGACUCCUGUGCUCUCUUUUCAGUGUCAUGGAACUGGUUUUGAAGAGACACUCUGAAAUGAUAAAGACAGCCUUUAAUCCCCCUCCUCCCCAGAAGGAACCUCAAAAGGUAGAUGAGGUACAAGGUCCUAAGUGAUCUCUUUUUCUGAGCAGGAUAUCAGGUUAAAAAAAAAAAGUUACUGGCUGGUUUAAUACUUUCUACCUUCUUCACAGAGCAGCCUUUGAAUAGACUAUGUCCUAGUGAAGACAUCAACCUCCGCCUUAAGCUAUGUAUGUAUGGAGGCCAGUCGCAGCUUUAUUAUGCAGACACACAAGUGGUCUGGACAUGAGGGUACAGUUUCUGCCUACCAAGACACUACUUGCACUGGAUCUUACGCAAAAAAGAACCAGAACACACAGUGUGGACAACUGCCCAUAUAUUCUAUCUAGAUUAGGAGAGGGUCCUGGCUAGGAUUUUAGUGGUAAUUCCUAGUUACAUUCAACAAGUAUAAAGAUUAUAGAGCUUAUUUUAUGAACUAUAAACUAUAAUUUAAUGCAAAAUAUCCUUUUAUGAAUUUCAUGUUAAUAUUGUGAAAUAUUAAAAUAAUUCCACAAUAGUUGAGAAAAAUGAGCAUUUUUUUCCAUUUUUAAAAAAUGCAUAGAAAAGACAAUUUUAAAAUCCUGGGACCAUAUUUAUUUAGAAGUAGCUGUUAGUAAAACAUUAGAAAAGGAGUCAGGCCAUUAGGUUAUUUAUCCAAAUCUCUAAGCAAUUAGGUUGAAGUUAUUAAGUCAAGCCUAGAAAAGCUGCCUCCUUGUAAGGCUUUCAUGACAAUGUAUAGUAAUCCACAGUGUCCAAUUCUUCACACUCCUCAGGAAUAUCACUACCUCAGGUUACGGUACACAGGCUAUAAUUGAUGAUGAUGUUCAGAUAACUGAAGACACAAUAAAUGACAUUCAGACAUCAGGACAAUUCCCUCAUGUUCUUUUCUAUGAUGGCCACCUGUACCAGCAACGUGGGUUUCACCCACACAACGAUGAACUGUUCUCUUACUUCUCCAGUUGAUUUUAAAGACUUGUUAAGAGGUCUUACUAAUAAAAUUUGGGUAUGAUAGAAAAUCCACAAUCAAAUCUUGAACCAAAUAACAUAUUAAAUUACUAAUAUUUAAGUGAUGGAAGACACACAAAAAACUUAAAAGCACGAACAACCUAACUUGAAAAAGAAUUUUAAAAUAUGAUUAACCUGAAGAAAAGAGAAUCCUAAGAGCCAAAGCUCCUUUUUAUUUAGCUUGGAAUUUUCCUAUUGGUUCCUAACAAACUGUCCCAAUGUCAUAUAAGGAAACAUGAUCUAUUACAUUCCUUUAUAACAAUGUGGAGAGACUAUAAACCUAUGUAAGUAGUAAAACUAUAUCAGAGACUCAGGAGACUGACUAAAAGGCCUGGAUCUGCAGUGUAUUAUCUGUAUAAAAAUUGGCAGGGGGAAGCUAAAAGGAAAGGAGAUUGGAGAUCUCAAUUCUAUCAUGGUGUAUUUCAUACGCAAAUCAGAGCAUGCAUUGUUUUUUGUUUUUGGAAAGAGAAGGGAAGUGUGUUCUGCCCCAUGUUUCCUUCCGUGUUUAUAGUUCAAACUCUAUAUAUACUUCAGGUAUUUUUUGUUUAGCCCUUCAUUAUAAAUGGGCAGGAAAUUGUUUAUCAACCUAGCCAGUUUAUUACUAGUGACCUUGACUUCAGUAUCUUGAGCAUUCUUUUAUAUUUUUCUUUUAUUAUCCUGAGUCUGUAACUAAACAAUUUUGUCUUCAAAUUUUUAUCCAAUAUCCAUUGCACCACACCAAAUCAAGCUUCUUGAUUUUCAAAAAUAAAAAGGGGGAAAUACUUACAACUUGUACAUAUAUAUUCACAGUUUUUAUUUAUAAAAAAAAUUUACAGUACUUAUGGAGAGCCAGCAGAAGACAUCAGAGCACUCACUUCUUCCCAUCUUUGUUAAGGUUAGCGAAUUACCCAUGGACACUGUUAGGUGAGGCUCAUUCGGCAGCCCUGAAAACAAACCUGGUCACACUGUCUUUACCCUCUCCCUUCAGAUAAAGCACUUCGAUUAUCUAUUGAUCUGCCCAGUUUUCAAGUCAUGCGAAUACUAAAAAGGUUACAUCAUCUGGAUCUGUACCUUGGCUAUAUAAGCAUGUUUUCCCCCUAUUCUAUGUUUCUUUUUUUGGUGAACAUUGAAAAACAGGAGGUGACUUAUUACUGUUAAUUAAAACUAAAUGAAAAAUGUCAAGUCUUUAAAACAGUGAGCUUGUAACUCUUUCAUGUAAUUUUAUUCUCUAUGAAUUUGGCUAUCCUACUGAAUCUUAAAAUAAAGGAAAUAAACACUUUUUUUUUAAAAAAAAGGAAAAAUACAAGUCUAAAAAUCUCAAUGAAAUAUUUCACAAGAAGGAAAAAUGUAAGUUAGCCUUUGCUUUCCACUUUGGAAUAAGCAGGAGGUUAGGGAAGGCAUUGAGAAGAAAAAAGAUAAAAAUAAUAUGUGUUGUUCAGUGCAGUGCCUAAGCUAGGUUUUCAAGAUUUUAUAAUACAGUAAGGAAAAUGUACUAUAUAUGGAGAUUAGGAUGUUGCAAUUUUUCCACAAAGGUUUAAAAACAUUUUGGAAAUACAAGUUUUUGUGGAACAUUGUGUUGGAAUAUUGUCCCCAUUAAGUUUCUCCUGAGAAGCUAAUUGGACUCUCCACUCAGCUUUAUUUCUAGGUAUAAUCACUGUUGGUUACACUAAACUCCUAAACCUAAAUGACAGGGCACAACUACAGCUUGAUCCUGUAUUACCACAUCAGGGCUCCUGGGUGAGCCAGAGACACUGUUUCAUAAAUGCAUAUUUAUUAUAACUUUAAGAGUAGCAAUCUCAUAUACUGAAUAGUCACUCUUUAACUCCAUUAAAUAAGAUACAGCAAGGGGAAGGACAGUAUCACACAAAAUGGCUUUCAAAUUCAAGUGGGGCUAUUUGAUAAUUACACUGUGGCACAGAGGCAGCUUAUGGGCACUUCUUGUUAAAACAUCUCCAUGUUACCAACUUCUGACAAGACUCUUAGUAUAGGCUUGGGCAUCAACCCAAGAUUAAAGUCAAGAACCUCAAUCACUUCUCUACAACUACAGGUGUUGAGUCUUUCCAGAAAAACAAAGGUCCAAAUGAGGCACCAUUCAUCACAGCUUCUUUCUCAUUUCCAUCUAGUGGGUAAGAGGUUUCUCUUCUUAAAACUACAAUUUCUUAACCUUUACAAGUUAUUUAACAUUUUCUAUCAUAUUAAAUUAGCAACAUAAAACAUUAUCCUUUAUCUAUAAACUUCUAGUCUGGUUCCCUAGAGUUUAUAUACACGUUUUUAUUUCUAAUCUGCAAGAAAAAAAAUUCCUAUUUGUUAUUUGGUAACAGAGCAUUAAAAGAUACUAUACACAUGUGGUGCAUAUAUAUAUAUAUAUAUACACACACACACACACACACACACAAAAUACACUUCAAAAAGAAGCCAACACACUUUAGCCAAAGUCUU